CUUCCUCCCGGCACAGAAGGCCUCCCCCUCUCACCAGGGCCCUCGCCCGCUGGUCCGCCAGGCCCCGCCUUUUUUGCGGCCCCCAUUGUGCUGCUGGACCCGACGAGCAGUGUUGACAGUGAACCCCACGUAGACGCGGCCCCGGUACCGGGGGUUCAGGCAGUAGAGCAGGUAGACGCCGAAAAAGCGCCCUGGCCUCGCCGCGACCCCCGCGGGACCCAUCGGGCCUUGGGGUUCGGGAACCACAGCAGGGGGUUGAUUGCCGUGACCUAGGGUCCAGGGGAGGGCUGGAUCGCUAGGGCUGCAGGGUGCUUGCUUCGGAACAAGCUCUCGGGGACUAUCCGGAGGCAGCCUGCAGGAAGCCGUAGCGCCGGUACGUGCCCCUCUCCUGUCUGGAGGCGGGUGUAGAAGUCCGACCGCGGAAGCCAGACUGCUGUCCAGUCGGCGAGCGCGUACCAUUCAGCAUCGGCUCCGCCCGAGUCCCACCUUCCUCAGGCUCUGAUUGGCUGACACAUGGCAAGCGCGAAAAGCCUGGACCGCUGGAAAGCCCGGCUGCUUGAGGGCGGAAGUACUGCGUUGACGUACGCCUUAGUAAGGGCGGAAGUGAGUUUUCCAGCGGAAGUGGCUCCUGUAAGGCAGCAAGGUAGCGUGGCCGGCGCCCGAGCUGGGGUUGUGUCCCUGCUGGGCUGCCGUUCCAGCUGGACUGCCGCCAUGGAACUCAGCGCCGAAUACCUCCGCGAGAAGCUGCAGCGGGACCUGGAGGCGGAGCAUGUGGAGGUGGAGGACACGACCCUCAACCGUUGCUCCUGUAGCUUCCGAGUCCUGGUGGUGUCGGCCAAGUUCGAGGGGAAACCGCUGCUUCAGAGACACAGGUUCUGUACAGAGUAAUGAGAUGUGUGACGGCUGCAAACCAGGUGUUUUUUUCUGAGGCUGUGUUGACAGCUGCUAAUGAGUGUGUUGGUGUUUUGCUCGGCAGCUUGGAUCCUAGCAUGACUAUACAUUGUGACAUGGUCAUUACAUAUGGAUUAGACCAACUGGAGAAUUGCCAGACUUGUGGUACCGAUUAUAUCAUCUCAGUCUUGAAUUUACUCACGCUGAUUGUUGAACAGAUAAAUACGAAACUGCCAUCAUCAUUUGUAGAAAAACUGUUUAUACCAUCAUCUAAACUACUAUUCUUGCGUUAUCAUAAAGAAAAAGAGGUUGUUGCUGUAGCCCAUGCUGUUUAUCAAGCAAUGCUCAGCUUGAAGAAUAUUCCUGUUUUGGAGACUGCCUAUAAGUUAAUAUUGGGAGAAAUGACUUGUGCCCUAAACAACCUCCUGCACAGUCUGCAACUUCCUGAGGCCUGUUCUGAAAUAAAACAUGAGGCUUUUAAGAAUCAUGUGUUCAAUGUAGACAAUGCAAAAUUUGUAGUUAAAUUUGACCUCAGUGCCCUGACUACAAUUGGAAAUGCCAAAAACUCGAGUCUUUAAUUGUAAUGACUUUGUUUUAUCCACAGUUAAGCCUUUUCUCAUUACAUAUUUAUGUAUUUCACUGUCAUGUCAACAUGUCUGCAGAAUCACUGUAUGUAACAAACAGCCAUAUUUAAGACAUGCCUGGAUAAAUAAAAUUGGUAGGAAUGUUUUCUUGCCAUUAUAUUUAACGUUUCUUCUUUUUCCUUGACAAAUCUUGAUAAGUUUUUUUAUAUUAGUUUUAUUUUCUAGAAAACGUCUUAUGAAUUUCUCCCAUUUGCUCUAGCAUGCUUAUAGAAAAUGUCAGUGUUUCUUACAGCUCAAAUUUGUAUAGUUGUUUUAAAAUGCGGUCUCUUUCUUCUUCCCCUGGUACUUUUUUCUUUCUGUCUACUGAAGUUAGUUCUUAUACAUGGUCUUAUAUUUUGGCUGUCUUUUUUUCCCUAGGAACAUUCAUACAGGUUGAAUAUUCCUUAUCUGAAAUACUUGGGACUGGAAGUGUUUUUGAUUUUGGAGUUUGGAAUACUUUUUUUUUUUU